AGUUAUAACAGAGACUAAAGAAGAAAGACGCUUACUGAAUAAGGUGGGAUCCAACAAGAGUGUAGUAUGGAAUGCAAUAGCUUAUGAAUUACUUUUUUUCUGAGGGAGCUCAACAGAAUGACACCUAAGAAAGGGAAAGUCUUUGACACUUGGUACGUUUGUGAUUUUUGGUCAUUACUUGAAAAUUAAUAAGUUUGAAAUCACUACUCUUAGAAAUGGAAGAAAGUGAUGACUCUAAUCAGCCUAUCUCAGCGUGUAGGCAAGAAAUUCGAAAGAGAAGAUGACCCAGCAAACCAAUGGUAGGCAAAUCCCAGCAAACUGAUGUAAUAGAGAAAAAGAAACACAUGGCCAUACCAAAAUCAUCUAGCCCCAAAGCUACCCAUCGUAUUGGUAAUACUUCUGGAAGCAAAGGCAGCUACUCUGCCAAAGCCUAUGAGUCUAUUAGAGUAUCUUCUGAGCUUCAGCAAACUUGGACAAAGAGAAAGCAUGGACAGGAAAUGACUAGUAAGUCUCUCCAGACAGACACCAUUGUAGAAGAGAAAAAAGAAGUCAAGUUAGUUGAGGAAACCGUGGUACCUGAAGAAAAGUCAGCUGAUGUUAGAGAAGCUGCUAUUGAAUUGCCAGAGAGUGUUCAGGAUGUAGAAAUUCCACCAAACAUACCUUCAGUUCAACUAAAAAUGGACAGAUCUCAGCAGACCAGCCGUACAGGAUACUGGACCAUGAUGAACAUCCCCCCUGUAGAAAAAGUGGACAAGGAACAACAGACAUACUUUAGUGAAUCAGAAAUAGUGGUUAUUUCCAGGCCAGAUAGUUCUUCUACAAAGUCAAAGGAAGAUGCCCUGAAACAUAAAUCGUCGGGAAAGAUUUUUGCUAGUGAACACCCUGAAUUUCAACCAGCAACAAACAGCAAUGAAGAAAUUGGGCAGAAAAAUAUCAGCAGAACUUCAUUUACUCAGGAGACUAAAAAAGGUCCCCCGGUACUUUUAGAAGAUGAGCUUAGGGAAGAAGUAACUGUACCUGUUGUACAAGAAGGUUCUGCUGUUAAAAAAGUGGCUUCUGCUGAAAUAGAGCCUCCAUCAACAGAAAAAUUCCCAGCUAAAAUACAGCCUCCAUUAGUUGAAGAGGCCACUGCUAAAGCGGAGCCCAGACCUGCUGAAGAGACCCAUGUCCAAGUACAGCCAUCAACUGAAGAGACUCCUGAUGCUGAGGCAGCCACUGCAGUUGCGGAGAAUUCUGUUAAAGUUCAGCCUCCACCUGCUGAAGAGGCCCCUUUAGUGGAGUUUCCUGCUGAAAUUCAGCCUCCAUCAGCUGAAGAGUCUCCUUCUGUAGAGCUUCUGGCUGAAAUUCUGCCUCCAUCAGCUGAAGAGUCCCCUUCAGAAGAGCCUCCUGCUGAAAUUCUGCCUCCACCAGCUGAAAAGUCUCCUUCAGUAGAGCUUCUUGGUGAAAUUCGGUCUCCCUCAGCACAAAAGGCUCCCAUUGAAGUACAGCCUUUACCAGCUGAGGGCGCCCUUGAAGAGGCCCCAGCUAAAGUAGAGCCUCCCACUGUUGAAGAGACCCUUGCUGAUGUUCAGCCUCUAUUACCUGAAGAGGCUCCUAGAGAAGAGGCUCGAGAACUUCAGCUUUCAACAGCUAUGGAGACCCCUGCAGAAGAGGCUCCUACUGAAUUUCAGUCUCCAUUACCUAAAGAGACCACUGCAGAAGAGGCCUCUGCUGAAAUUCAGCUUCUAGCAGCUACGGAGCCUCCUGCAGAUGAAACUCCUGCCGAAGCUCGGUCUCCACUAUCUGAGGAGACUUCUGCAGAAGAGGCUCAUGCUGAAGUUCAAUCUCCAUUAGCUGAAGAGACCACUGCAGAAGAGGCCUCUGCUGAAAUUCAGCUUCUAGCAGCUAUAGAGGCUCCUGCAGAUGAAACUCCUGCUGAAGCUCAGUCUCCACUAUCUGAGGAGACUUCUGCAGAAGAGGCUCCUGCUGAAGUUCAGUCUCCAUCAGCUAAGGGAGUUUCUAUAGAAGAGGCCCCUCUUGAGCUUCAGCCUCCAUCAGGUGAAGAGACCACUGCAGAAGAGGCCUCUGCUGCAAUUCAGCUUCUAGCAGCUACAGAGGCUUCUGCAGAAGAGGCUCCUGCUGAAGUUCAGCCUCCACCAGCUGAGGAGGCCCCCGCUGAAGUUCAGCCUCCACCAGCUGAGGAGGCCCCCGCUGAAGUUCAGCCUCCACCAGCUGAGGAGGCCCCCGCUGAAGUUCAGCCUCCACCAGCUGAGGAGGCCCCCGCUGAAGUUCAGCCUCCACCAGCUGAGGAGGCCCCCGCUGAAGUUCAGCCUCCACCAGCUGAGGAGGCCCCUGCUGAAGUUCAGUCUCUACCAGCUGAGGAGACUCCUAUAGAAGAGACCCUUGCUGCAGUACACUCUCCCCCAGCUGAUGAUGUCCCUGCAGAAGAGGCCUCCGUUGACAAACAUUCCCCACCAGCUGAUUUGCUUCUGACUGAGGAGUUUCCUAUAGGAGAGGCCUCUGCUGAAGUUUCACCUCCACCAUCUGAACAAACCCCUGAAGAUGAGGCUCUGGUAGAGAAUGUGUCUACAGAAUUUCAGUCACCGCAGGUGGCAGGAAUUCCAGCAGUAAAAUUAGGAUCGGUUGUUUUGGAAGGUGAAGCAAAAUUUGAAGAGGUUUCAAAAAUCAAUUCUGUCCUUAAAGAUUUGUCUAAUACCAAUGAUGGACAGGCUCCCACUCUUGAAAUAGAAAGUGUUUUUCAUAUAGAAUUAAAACAACGUCCUCCUGAACUGUAGUCAGGUUGUACCUAAGCUAGCAAUCAGAAGCUACAUGGUUUUGGAAGAACAUACUUUAGAAAAGGGUGGGCAGCGGGAAGUAGCUUUGUCAAUAAGGCAAAUUAAAGGGGACCCCAAGACUUGGAAUACAGGUUGGAAAAUGAACAAUAAAAACUGUAGCAGCAUAAAAUUACUUGUGUUAAUUUCAUUCAAAUUUAUGGCAUGAAAAAUACCUAUUUUGAAAGUAAGUUUAUAAUUGAAAAAAAUUGCUUAAAAUAUCCUUCCUACAGUAAACUUGUUGACACGAGUAAAGUUUAAUCUGCAGCCAUCUUUUCUUGUCUUUGCCUUCCCUUUAUAAGUAAAUAUAGUUUCUAGUGGAAAA